AUGAAGCACCAAGAAACAAGGUUUCGCUACACCGAGAAAACGACGCCGGCCCCGGGAAGCAGCCUCCCCGCCUUGGAGUCCGGUUGGGGCGUGAGGGCCGCGCGGGUCCCACGCCCCAAGGCUAAGCAGCCGAAAGCACAGCGCGCUCGGGGCCAAACCGGGCUGUAUCGCAGGCGCAGAUGGCGCGUCGGGCGGAAGCUGGAGGCCGCCGGCUCAACACGCUCCGUACCCGGGACUGGGGCCCGGCCUGCAGCCUCAGCGAGCAGGCGACAAGGGCGGCGCCACAGAGGCCGACGCGUCCCCCGCCCGCCUGAGCGCGCCGCAACAGCCACCUCGUCCCACCCGCCCCGGGGCGGGGCCGGGGGCGCGGCGCCGGGGCCCUCUGGCCCCCUCCGGUCUCGCCGGCCCCGCCCCCUCCCUGUCCCCGUCCCCGAGGGGCUGAGGGGGAGGGAGGGGCGACGCACUCCGGCCGCGUUGCACGCUCGCCGCUUCCCUCAGUCCCGCGUGCGCGCGCGCGCUCGCCCCAAGUCCCGCGGACUGGGAGAAGCGCCAGAGAGGCCGGGCCUGCUCCGGUCGGACCGGAUCCCUCCCCUCCCCCUCCCUCCUCCCUCCCCUCCCCCAAACCCACUUCCGCAGCUCGCGGCCUUGCCGCCGAAGCAGCAGCGGCGGCAGCAGCAGGAGGCGGCGGCGAGGCGUCGGAAGGAUUACGCACCUGACGGGCCCGCCUCUGAGGGCUCCAGCGCGGGACGCUCACCGGCCGCCGCCGCCCAGGGCGCACUUCGCGGUGGCGGCGGGAAGGGAGGGACCGGCCACGGGGAACCGAACGCGAAUCGCCCCCCUCCCCUUCCUCCCUCCCACCCUCCCUCCGAUCCGCCGCCCGCCCUCUCGGCUUCCGUCCCCUCCCCCUCCCACAAAACCCCGGAUGGAGGCGCCGCCGACUCGCCGCCGCCUGGCUCCGGGGGAUGGUUUUGUCAAGCGGCCAGAGCCCCGGCGCCAGGCGCAGCCGCCGCCGCCCCCGCGAGGCGCCCCUGCCCUCGCUUCCCAGAACCGGGUCCCCGAGUGGCCCGGGCCUUCCGCCUGCCUGCACCCGUAGCCCUGGUACGAGGGUCAUUCGUCGUCUUUGUUGCCACCGCCUCUGCCGGAACCGUUUGCGAGCUCCGGUGGCCCCCGCCCCCCCACCGCCUUCCCGGACCCUGGGCUGGGGGUGGCACGUGGGCACCGGCCCCGGGAGGCGGAGGCGGUGCGCGCUUACCUGUCGCCGGUGCUGCUGCGGCGGGGGGUGUGGAGGAGGCGCCUCUGGGCAGCCUCGGCCGUGCUGUCCUCCCCGCCGCCGCCGCCUCUGCCUCUCGCUGCUGCUGCUGCUGCUGCCGCCGCGGUCGGUGUCUCCGGCGCGGCGGCGGCGGCGGCGGCGGGGCUUUUCCUGUCCGGUUACGUUAAGGUCACAUGACCGAGAGAGCGGAGAGACUAGUGCAAAGAGGCUGCGAGCGGCUCCCGCCGGGGGGGAGAGGCGGCGAGAGAGCAGUGGCGGCAAGAGCCCCCUCCGCCCCCCCCCCAGCCGCUCCCCUCCCCCCGCCCGCCUCCGCCUCCUGCUGCUCUGCCGCCGCCGCCGCCGCCUGCAGCACUCCACUGCCGCUCCCACCCAGGCUCCGCGCUCUGCUCCAGCCAAACUUCUGCAGACCAUGUGCAGCCGAGGCGAGGAAACUUCUCUCCACCUAUUGGGGCUGGAGGCCUGAGUCACAAGCCCCUUGUUUACAUAAAGUGUUUAGGUAGCACAAGUCCUUGAGAUGCUCGGGGUAGAGAUGGAGAGCCACUGCUCGUAUCCUUCUGCCGGCUUCUGCUUGAGAUCUCUUGGCCUUUACCCUUGUCCCUUGACUUUUCGUGUUUGUUUUAAUCUUUAAGACUUGAAAUGGAGUGGCCUUUAGAACCGGGGAGAUACUGUAAACCAGCAGUAUCUUUGUGUCACCAAUGGUAACUGAAAGUCAUGCUGAAGUACAGAUUCCUGUAGCGUGCACAGAGGCAGAGGUGCUUCCUUUACCUUGCAGAUGAGUUGAGCGGCGUAAGAUGUUUCUGUUAGGGUUGAAUUUCAUGGUUAUUUCAGCAACGAUUUUCGUUUUUGAAGUUUUGGCCCCCCCAAAAAUGAAAGUCUGCAACGCAUGUUUGUUAAGAGAACAGUUUAUUCUCCUGUUAGGUUUUGGUCUUUGAGGUAUGGAUUCCAGAGUUGGCUAUUCUGUUAGAUUUAGAGGUGUGGAAAAUCUUUUAACGGGGAGAUCCUGAAACACGGAAACAUGGCAGGGAAGUUAGAAUUUCCUGAUGGUCAUUUUUAACAUUUUAAAGUUUACUUUUUGGUUGUUGCCAUUUUUCUAGAAUCCGUGUCUUUUUUGGGGAAAUACAGUCCUUUGAGGACUAGAAUUUAAUGAUUUCUUUACACAUCUAGGAUUUUUUGAGAUUUAGAAAGGAUAUGGCUUUAUUCCUAAGGAAGUGGAGGCAGCAGUUUCUAGGAUACUCUGGUUUCAAGGCAUGCUAACUUGGUUGUGAUGUCUAACCCAUUUUGGUUUACACAGUCUGACCACUAGCACAAUGCCUGGCACAUAGUUUACAAAUCAUUUAAGGCAAGCUUACCAUCUUAAGACAAUUUAAUACAUAGAAGUGUCCCUCCUAAAAAUCUGAGUUUGAUUUAGAAAUCCAGUUAUACCUGCAGGUACUGAUGACUAAUUCCUUCUUUGAAGACAAAAUAAGCAGCUGUGUAGCUUCAGUGGCUCUCAAAUGGAUAAUAGAUUCAGUGUAUACUCGCUUUGAACUUUCCUGUUUUUUGAUCAGCUAGAUAAAUGACUUUAGUGGGUAAAUGUCUGCCUCCAAAACCAAAUUCUGACCCUGAUCUAAGUAUUCUACUGCACCGCUGUCACUGGAAUAUCAAAGUUGGCCUUCAGACUGGUGCCUGGUUCCUUGGAUUGGCUUGAGUAUUGAGGUCUGUCUCAUCUUACUAGGGAACUAAAAUGAUGUUGAUUGUUUUGUAGAGAAUUGUAAUUAGAGAUCUGUAGGUUCUUAAUUCUUUUGGAAUUCCAUUCUGAAAAUUUUCAACCUUAUGGUGUUGGUGGAGUGCUCAUGUGAAGAGUGAAACUGACUUAAGAAUAAAAGAAAAAGUGGGCAAAACUAAUGCUAAACUUGAGACCAUUGGGCAGAAAUUUGCCUGUGUGUGUAGAGUAAUUGGUCUUGAGUCAAAGUAACUAUGCUUAUUUUUAACAUCACUGAAUAUUUUCUAGCGUUACACUCUAUAUAGGCUUGUAGAAAUAAACCCAGGGGUAAGCCCAGAAAUUGAAUAUCAGUCCUAAAGAAAGCCUAUCAAGAGCAUCCUAUUCUCUUUAAGAGCUGCUAUUCGAAUUUAGGACUGGGCUGGUUUGCUGCUCAUUCUCUCGAGGCAUAGGCAGCCACACUUGAAUUUUGCCAAGUAUGCAGAUAAUUCCAACUUGUAGUCAGGAUCAUCAGGUAAUAGCAUUAUAAGGGGAGCUGUACAGACUGUAUACUUUCUACAGUUUGUUGAAAUAGAAACAUUUAUAUGGAUACAUACAUCUGCAAAGGUUAGGGAGAAAACGGUAGCCCUGGCAGAGAAGAGCUAGUUAGUGUAUUUCAGGAUAGGGCCAAGGGAAGCUGUCAUUUCUCUACUAAGUCUCAUUGUGGAAAAGCCACAAAUGUCCCUAGUACAGUAAUAAGGAAAAAAAGGCUGAGCGUGGUGGCUCACACCUGUAGUCCCAGGACUUUCGGAAGGAUUGCUUGAGCCCAGGAGUUGCAGAUCGGCCAGGACAAUGUAAGAAAACCCCAUGUAUUAGAAAAAAAGAAUUAGCCAGGCGUGAUGGUGUGGGUCUAUAGUCUCAGCUUGGGAGGCUGAGGUGGCAGGAUCGCAUAUAGCCCAGGAGUUCGAGGCUGCAGUGAGCCAUGAUCGCAUCACUGCACCCUAGUCUGGGCAACAGAGUCUCUAAAAAGGAAAAAAAAAAAAAAAGUUAAAUCGCUGUUUAAUUAUGUGCCAAUUUAUUUUGGUAUUUUGAGAAUCUGGUAAAUUAGGAAUUCAAAAAUAGUUUUAACACUUUUUACUUCAAAGAAAAUCACAGUGCAAGCAAUCUGAGUGGAUUCAUCAAAAGUUAUACAUGAAUAUUCUGCAGAGUCUGGUGUUGCUGAAAGUUUUGAUUUGUGUUCUGCUGAGACACAACCAUGAAAAUAUGCACUUGCUUGUAUUCCGAAGAGGAUAGUUCCAGUGAGACUUGGACAAUGAGCAGAAAAAAUUUUUUUUUGAGACGAGGUGUCGCUGUGUCGCCCAGGCUGGAGUGCAGCGGCGCGAUAUCUGCUCACUGCAACCUCUGCCUCCUGGGUUCAAGCGAUUCUCAUGCCUCAGCCUCCCAAGUAGCUGGGACUACAGGUGCCCGCCACCACACCCGGCUAAUUUUUUGUAUUUUUUUUUUUUUAGUAGAGACGGGGUUUCGCAGUGUUAGCCAGGAUGGUCUCGAUCUCCUGACCUCGUGAUCCACCCGCCUCGGCCUUCCAAAGUGCUGGGAUUACAGGUGUGAGCCAUUGUGCCCAGCUCAGAAAAUUUAAUAGUACUAGAUCUCGUGUGUGUGUGUGUGUGUGUGUGCGCGCGCUUAGGUUGAAGGUGGAAUUUAACAUUGAUUUAAAAAAAAUAAUAGUAGGAAAAAAUAAAUGCGGUUUGAGUCCAAAGCAGCAUUUUUCACUAAUUUUAUGAAGGAAGUCCUUUUGAGUAAUGUCUUAAAUUAGGAAAAUGGCGUACUUUUACAUGUUAGACAUUAAACUCUAGGGCAGAUAACCAUGCCCUGUGUGUUGUGUAUCAAGCUUAGCAUAUACAUAGGAAAAGAUGUAUUGUGAGAGUGUCUUACAUUUCGUUGGUUUGGUCAUAAAGUUUAUAGAAAAUGCUUGUUUUAUAGUUGGUUGUUAUUGAGAUGAGAGUCCCUCAAGGAACUCCCUAUGCUUUAGGGAGCUUUUUGUUUUAAACCUACUGGUUAGACUUGUGGGUUUUAAUGUUUUCAGCUGUGGUUGUAAGAAACACAUUUUAAAUUGCACCUAGUAUAGACAUACAUGUAAAACAAACAAAAUUUUUACGAAGUAGUACUUGUAUUAAGAGUGAUGUACUCUGCUAUCUUCUAUUUCAUUUUUUUAAAGUUGAUAUUGCUGCCUUAAAUUGAUUUUUUCAACCACUAAUGAGUCAGGACCCACUAUUUAAAAAAUACUGGUGUGUUCUCUUGCUGUUACGAAUUAACCCAAAACUUAGUGGUUUAAAGCAAUAAACUUGUGUUUAUCUCAUGUAGGUUCUGUGGGUCAGGAAUCUGGGAGUAGCUUACUUAGGUGGUUCUGGGUCAGGGUUUUUCAUGAGGUUCCAAGGUGGCUCUCAUUUGGCAAGUCAGCUAUGGCUGAUGGUGGAAGUUCUUCAUUGGACUGCUUGAGUGUCCUCAAGCAGUGGCGAAGGCUAGCUACCCGCAGAGUAGGUGAUUCAAGCAAGAGCAGAGAGGAGGCCACACACCAUCACUUCUGCCAUAUUCUAUUAAAAAGAAGUCACUUAAGUCCAGCCCAAACUCAGGGGAUGAGUAUCAAAGAAUUAUGGACAUAGUUUAAUAGCUGCCACAUUUAUAUGUUUUUCCACUUUAUAUUUUAUUUAUUUAUUUAUUUAGAGAUGGAGUCUUGCUCUGUCGCCCAGGCUGGAGUGCAGUGGCGUCAUCUCAGCUCACUGCAGCCUCUGCCUCCCGGGUUCAAGUGAUUGUCCUGCCUCAGCCUCCCUAGUAGCUGGAAUUAUAGGUGCCCCCUACCACGUCCGGCUAAUUUUGUAUUUUUAGUAGAGAUGGGGUUUCACUAUAUUGGCCAGGCUGGUCUCGAACUCUUGAACUCAGGUGAUCCACCUGCCUCAGCCUCCCAAAGUGCUGGGAUUUCAGGCAUGAGCCACCACCCUGGCCUGUUUUUCCAUUUUAAAGAUGAGUUAGGAUUGCACCAAAAGCCAUGCUGAAAUCAACCUAUAAGUAAUUAUCUUAGUUAAUUAAGUCAGUUUUUUUCUCUGAGGGCAUCUAGUCACACUUCCUUCUCAGUCUUCAAUUUGAAAAAGCAGGCUCAAAGAAUUUAAGUAAUUAAGCAGCCCAAGGUCAUUCAGUCUAGGAAAACCUCACAAAUUUUCUCUGACCUUUGUCAUGAAUAACAUGUGAGCUGAUAAAGAUGAGAAAAUUAAGAAGUUACACUGUAGAACUGUUCGCCAGUCUUCUAGUUUGCAGACCUCCAUAUUAUAAUACACUUUAAAAUUCAGAUAAUGCUUGGUGUCUAGAUUCCUCAUACUAGCACCCCUCCUGUUCAUUUUUAGAGGAAACAGGAAAUGUACUUAUUAAAUGAAUUCAAACUACUUUGAAUAGACCAUUCCAGAUGCUGCCUGUAUACUCACUAUGAGAUGUACUGUGCAAACUAAUUCCAAUUAGCACAUUUUGAGAACCCAAAAGGAUGUUGUGACUUAAAGAUGAUGAGAAUUUAAGUGUAAAGAAGACUACACUUCUUUAUGCUGUGAAAUUUUCAUAGAAAUUUUGGAUCUGGAAGGAUUUUGUUCUAAGACUAGUUUUAGCUUAGUGAUAAAAGGAAUAGGAUGACAUUGGUAGUGAGCGAAGGCAGGAUAAAUUUCUAAAGACUUCCUUAAAAAUUUUUUUAAUCCAUUAGGCUUUUCUAAAUUAUAGGUUGGGAUACAAUAAGUUAUCUUACACCUUUGCUUCACGGAAUGGGCUAAUGGCUACUUUUUUUUUUUUUUUUUUUUUUUUUUUUGAGAUGGAGUCUUACUCCCAUCUCACAGGCUGGAGUGUAGUGGCACAAUCUUGGCUUACUGCAACCUCCACCUCCCGGGUUCAAGUGAUUCUCCUUCCUCAGCCUCCUGAGUAGCUGGGAUUAUAGGCGUGCACCACCACACCCGGCUAAUUUUUGUAUUUUUAGUAGAGAUGGGGUUUCACCAUGUUGGCCAGGCUGGUCUCGAACUCCUGACCUCAGGUGUGCCACCUGCCUUGGCCUCCCAAAGUGCUAGGAUUACAGGCAUGAGCCACUGCGCCUGGCCGGAUAAUGGCUACUUAAAUCAUUUUUCAGUUUUCCCUUACCACUAUGAUUCCUGACUGUUUCUAUUCUGACCUAAAGUACUGUUUGUACACAAUUAAUUUUGAUUACCCUUUUUGCUUGUUACUUGUCUCCCUAUAUCUUGUAUCUCUCACUCUCACUGUAAGCUCCCUGAGGGCAGGUACUUCUUUUUAUGUACACUCCUGGUACUCAAUUGCUUGCAGAAUUGAGUUGAAUUUGUAGUUAAAGGAUCUAAGAUGAUCAUUUUCCCACUCGAACUGAGUGAAAAAGGUGUUUAUUGUUGCAGAAAACAUCUGCGUAUAGGUAUUGGAUGCUAGUGGUGCAUAUAUGAAUACCUAUCUCUGCUCUUCAGGUGGUCACAGUCCACUGGGGGAGAAAAACACAGAUACUUAGUACAAUUUAUUCUAUACUGCAGAUGUGCAGAGUGCUGUGGGUAUGUAGAUAACUUUAAGCUGAAUCUUGGUCGGUGAGCAGGUGUUCAGAAGAUAGACUUAGUGGCCAAGUGCGGUGGCUCACGCCUGUAACCCCAGCACUUUGGGAGGCCGAGGCGGGUGGAUCACUUGAGGUAAGGAGAUCGAGACCAUCCUGGCCAACAUGGUGAAACCCCGUCUCUACUAAAAAUACAAAAAUUAGCUGGGCGUGGUGGUGCAUGCCUGUAAUCCCAGCUACUCGGGAGGCUGAGGCAGGAGAAGCGUUUGAACCAGGGAGUUGGAGGGUUGCAGUGAGCCGAGAUGUUGCCACUGCACUCUAGCCUGGUGACAGAGCGAGGCUCUGUAUCAAAAAAAAAAAAAAAAAAAAAGAUAGACUUAGUUUUGUGAUGUGCUUUGGGGGUGGUGCAUUUCUUAGCUUCAUUCCUUUACUAUACAUCUCCCUUGAAUUAUUUUCCUUUUAUCGUUGGUGAGUUACCAUCAUAAUUUAAUAAAUUGUUUCCUUCUGUGACAUGUACAUUCUUGUCACAUCAUUUCUCUAGAACUGUGCUGUCCAGUUCAACUCAGUGUCACACUAGCCAUGUGUGCUGAGUAGCCACCUGUGGCUAGAGGCUACCAUAUUUGGGCAGCACAGAUAAUAUAAAACAUUUCUAUUAUUGGAGAAAGUUCAGUUGGACAUCACUGCUCUAGAAUCAUGUUUUGCUUCUCCCUAUUUUCACGUUAUCAAUAGUGUAUUGAGUUCAGAAUAGAAUUAGGAAACAAUAGCCUCCUGAUAUUGUCAUUGGGAGGGAUAGAGUGGUUGAUAUUUAUGAACAGAGGGGGGAGAGUGUAGUGUUUGGUAGUGGUUGAGAAUAUAGCCUUUGGAAUCAGAUCUGGGUUGGAAUUAUGGUCCGUCCCUUACACACUGUAUGGCUUCGGGCAUGUUACUGAACCUCUGAGCCUCAAGUUUUCCUUCUCAAAUAGGGUUAAUAGUAAUUAUCUCAUAACAUUGGGUGAACAUAAAAACAGGAGGGGGGCCGUAGCACAGUACCUCAGUAAAUGAUAAAAUCGGUAUAUUUUUGAAAUCAUCACUGAUUUAAAAAAAAACCUUAGAAUUAUGUAGUAAAAGUGACUUUUUUUUUUCAGUAUACCGUUCUGUGAUUUUUAACAUAGUAUUUAUUUGUUGUAAUCACCAACACGAGAAUAUAGGCCAGGUCUAUCACUUUAUUUUGCUGUCUUUAUAGACCUGUGCUGUUUCCACCCCUAACCCCUGGCUGUCACCGAUCUGUUGUCCAUCACUAUAGUUUUACCUUUUCUAGGAUGUUACAUAAAUGGAAUUACACAGUAUGUCGCCUUUGCACACUGGCUUCCUUUACCCAGCCAGAUUGGGUUGAGAGCGAUUUGUCCAAGUUGUUACAUCUAUCAGUCGUUGAAAACUGAUCUUUAAAGACAUUUUAAUUUUGAAUCAUUAUUUCCUAAACGUGAAUCUGAAUUCCUUAACAGUUCUUCAAGUAGUGUUUGGCUCAGGAUUUUUGUGUUUAAAAGUAAAAUAAAUGGUAAAAUAUAUAGGGAAAAAUUACUGCUUCCACCUGAUUGGUAAAAACCAUGUGUGACAUUAACAUGCUUUUCUUUAGGGAAGGUUCUUGUUUUUAGUAGUUGAUCCAUAUUAAAGCUCUGUAGAGUUGCCACAAAGUCCAGAGUUGAAAAAGGUGGCUGUUAAAAUAUCAGUUUCUAAAAUGUGGCCGAAGAUAGCGUGACCAGUCCUGGUUUGCCCAGGACUUUGCCAGUAUUAGCAGUGAAAGUCUGGCCGCUCUCAGGAAACCCCUUGGUCCCAGUCAAACCCAGAAUGGGACCAAGCGCCGUGGCUCAUUCCUGUAAUCCCAGCACUUUGGAAGGCUGAAGUGGGCAGAUCACGAGGUCAGGAGUUUGAGAACAGCCUGGCCAAAAUGGUGAAACCCCGUCUCUAAUAAUAGCCUGACAUGGUGAUGCACGCCUGUAAUCCCAGCUGCUUGGGAGGCUGAGGCAGGAGAAUCGCUUGAACCCAGGAGGUAGAGCUUGCAGUGAGCCAAGAUUGUGCCAAUGCACUGCAGCCUGGGUGACAGACUGAGACUGUGUCUGAAAAACAAACAAACAAACAAAACCCCAGAAUGGUUGGUCACCCUAUCUGAAAAGAGACACACAAAAUCAGAGGAUUCCAGUUCAUCAGGUUUCAGUAGUGAACCAUCGGCCAAGUAUUUCAUCUAAUCUUAAUUGCCUUUGGGUGCUUAGAGUCAAAUCUCUAAGGUAACCAGAACCCAAACCACAUGAGGUUUUUUAGAUUAAGAUCAGCACCUUGAAUUUAAGGUUUUGUGGCUAGAGGUUUAGAUUUGAUUGGAAUUACAUCGUUAAUUUUUGUUAAAUUGUUGAAUAAGCAACUUCCCAAGCCUUGUGUGUAGAAGCUAGAUUAAAAGUCAAGUUUCUACUUAACCAGAAUCUCUGUUUUGAGUUUUUAAAUUCAACUGGUGAUGUCUAAAUCUUAAGGAUAUUGUAAGUUCCUUAACUAGUCUGUUCCAUUUUCCUGAGUUUUCACAUCACCUCUCUACCUCUUGUGUAGAUUUUAUUUUUUAUUUUGAAACGGAUUUUCGCUCUUGUUGCCCAGGCUGGAGUGCAGUGGCACCAUCUCGGCUCCGCAACCUCUGCCUCCUGGGUUCAAGCGAUUCUCCUCCCUCAGCCUCCUGAGUAGCUGGGUUUACAGGCACAUGCCAGCGCACCUGGCUAAUUUAGUAUUUUUAGUAGAGACGGGGUUUCUCCAUGUUGGUCAGGCUGGUCUCAAUUUCCGGACCUCAGGUGAUUUACCCGCCUCUGCCUCCCAAAGUGCUGGAAUUACAGGCAUAAGCCACCACGCCCAGCCCUAGAUUUCUUUAUAGAGCAUCUGUCUAUAAGCAGAUUACUUAGUUUUCCUGAUGUCUUCGUUGGAAUGUAAGCUUUGUGAAAGCCAGGGGCCCUAUGUGUCAUCUUUACCACUAUGUCUUAGAUCUUAGAGCAGCCCAUCAUAAGUUCUAAUAAGUAAUUGUGGAAUUGGAUGAGAAAAUGAAUAUGAGUCAGUUUUACAAUGCUGCAUGCUUCCCAGAUUAUUUUAACAGUCUAGGGGAUGUGGAAAGAUUUUGUUUUAAAAACGUUUAAAAGUCCACGUUUUGUUUGAUAUUGUUCAGAGGAAGUGAAAAUGUGGUCUUUAAAAAAUUUUGUUGCCCGGGUGUGGUGACUCACGCCUGUAAUCCCAGCACUUUGGGAGGCUGAGGCGGGUGGAUCACCUGAGGUCAGGAGUUCAAGACCAGCCUGGCCAACAUAGUGAAACCCCGCCUCUACUAAAAAUAUCAAAAAUUAGCUGGGCAUGGGGGUGGGCACCUGUAAUCCCAGCUGCUCGGGAGGCUGAGGCAGGAGAAUCGCUUGAACCCGGGAGGCGGAGGUUGCAGUGAGCGGAGAUCGCGCCAUUGCACUCCAGCCUGGGCCACAGAGCAAAACUCUGUCUUAAAAAAAAAAAAAAAAGGCUGGGCGCGGUGGCUCACGCCUGUAAUCCUAGCACUUUGGGAGGCCGAGGUGGGCAGAUCACGAGGUCAGGAGAUCGAGACCAUCCUGGCUAACACGGUGAAACCCCGUCUCUACUAAAAAUACAAAAAAUUAGCUGGGUGUGGUGGCAGGCACCUGUAAUCCCAGCUACUCGGGAGGCUGAGGCAGGAGAAUGGCGUGAACCUGGGAGGCAGGCGGAGCUUGCAGUGAGCCGAGAUCGUGCCACUGCACUCCAGCCUGGGUGAAAGUGUGAGACUCUCAAAAAAAAAAAUUGUUUCAUUAACCCUCUAUGAGGGAAGGGAAUUUAGAAUGGUGACAUUAAACCUUCCUUUAAAAUGGCAAUUCAGAACCAGUGGAGAGAGCUGAAAGUGAGAGUAGAUUUGGAUUUGGAAAAAUUCCCUCUACUUCUCAUACACAUCACCUUCUCCCAACACAGGCACUUUGUAAAGGCAUAGAGCAGGGUCUGAGGAGAUUGGGUUGGUGAAAGAGAGAACUGAGUCACUUGAGAUUAGUACUUGGUAAGCAAGAGAGUGCUAAUGAAUUAUUUAAAAUCUGUGUAACCUGAGUGUAAACCAAUACAUAGACUAAGUUAGUGCUUCUCAGAGCUUAGGGAGCAUAGGAGUCUCCUGGAGAAUUAGAAGAAACAGAUUUUCCUAGCUCCGGCCCCAGACGUUCUGAUUUAGUGUGGUGUAGAACUCAGGAGUUAGUAAUAUUAAUGGACAGUCUUGAGUAUUUGCUGAUGCAACUGGUCUGAGGACCAUACUUUGGAAGACCUGCUUUAGAUAGUAGACAGGACAGUAAUUUAAAAUAGGCAAAUAUGGUUUAUUUUUAAAAUGGUAAAACUAGAAAGAUACUGAUUUUAUGUGUUUAAAAAAAAAAGUCUGCAUCUGACUGCUAUGGUUAUCCAAGAAGGCACCCCAGAAUACCUGUUGGCCACCGCUGUUUGGUAUAUGCAAAAAUGUGUAGUUUUUAAAAGAGUCUUUUUGGGCUUGCACUGAGGAGCCACCCUAUUUUAUACAGUCAAAAUAUUGCUAUAUUUAAGUUAACCAUUCUGUUCCAGUGCAGGAUUCAGUAACAUCUAUUCUGUAAGUUUCAGUUGUGAUAUUUCUUAAAGAUUCAAAGAUGGAUCCUGGGAAUUUGAUUUAGCCUCCAUUUCAUCUGGGAGUUAAUCCUCACAGCAACCCUGUGAGAUAGGUUAAUAAUUAAACCCUCCUAUUCACACAUAUUUCAUUAAUCCUUACAGCAACCUGAGAGAUAGUUUAAUAAUUAAACCUACUCCACAGAUGAGGAAACUGAGGCCCAAGAGGUUCAGUGAUUCGCCCAAGGUUAUAACAGCAAGAAUUGGUGGUGAAACAAGAAUUCAAAUCCAGAUUGGUCUUAAUAGUGAGCUCUCAUGUGUGAUAGAAAUUAGAUACCACUUUGAGGACUUUGGGAGCCAGUGGUGAAUGUACUUACUUUAGGCUCUAAAUACUCUGUGUAAUUUCUUGGUCAUUUUGUUCUUAGAGAGGUGGUGAUCUUAAUAAAGUUUUGACUUUAUUAAGUAAUUAAAAGUUUUUACUUAUGUUACAACUAAAACAAUUCUUUAAAACUUUCAUAACUUGAAGUUUUAAAUCCUAAAAUUAGUUGAAAAAGAUGUAAUUGCCAGUGUAUCGUAAAUACUGGUAUUUUAAAAUAAAGCUGCUUUAUCACUUUUAAGGAAAGCCCUUGUAAUUUAGUGCAUUGUAAUAGUGUAUUGAGCUGAUGUCCACCAUGAUCCAUGUAAACAUAGGUGAACUAUGCAAAUACAAGUUUUUCUUCUUGAAAAUGUUACAUUUCCUCUACAACACUUUAUGCUAAUAAAUGUUUAUGAACCUCUUUUGAUGAUCCUUUCAUUUCUUGUAAAUUUUUGUAUAUAACUUGAAAUGUUUAAUUUGCUGUAAUCAUAAGGCAUCAAAUGUUCAUGGUUUUUUUCUGGACUAUUUUCACAUUGUUAGUACUGAUUAGUUGACCAAAACAGCAAAUUGCAUACAUUGAUACUUGCAGUAAAAUUUCACUGGAAUUGUACCUCCUAAAAAAAAUGGGAGAAAACAUAAUGGCUUCAAUUAAAGGAGGCUGCAUUUACCAAUCUU